AGGCUCCUAGGAGACCAGAAGCAGCAGCCUUUCCUGAGCUCAGGUGUUUUCGAUGGCGCAGCCACAGCUUCUGUGAGAUUCGAUUUCUCCCCAGUUCCCCUGUGGGUCUGAGGGGACCAGAAGGGCCUUACCUGCUGGGCACUAACGGCGGAGCCAGGAUGGGGACAGAAUAAAGGAGCCACGACCUGUGCCACCAACUCGCACUCAGACUCUGAACUCAGACCUGAAAUCUUCUCUUCACGGGAGGCUUGGCAGUUUUUCUUACUCCUGUGGUCUCCAGAUUUCAGGCCUAAGAUGAAAGCCUCUAGUCUUGCCUUCAGCCUUCUCUCUGCUGCGUUUUAUCUCCUAUGGACUCCUUCCACUGGACUGAAGACACUCAAUUUGGGAAGCUGUGUGAUCGCCACAAACCUUCAGGAAAUACGAAAUGGAUUUUCUGAGAUACGGGGCAGUGUGCAAGCCAAAGAUGGAAACAUUGACAUCAGAAUCUUAAGGAGGACUGAGUCUUUGCAAGACACAAAGCCUGCGAAUCGAUGCUGCCUCCUGCGCCAUUUGCUAAGACUCUAUCUGGACAGGGUAUUUAAAAACUACCAGACCCCUGACCAUUAUACUCUCCGGAAGAUCAGCAGCCUCGCCAAUUCCUUUCUUACCAUCAAGAAGGACCUCCGGCUCUGUCAUGCCCACAUGACAUGCCAUUGUGGGGAGGAAGCAAUGAAGAAAUACAGCCAGAUUCUGAGUCACUUUGAAAAGCUGGAACCUCAGGCAGCAGUUGUGAAGGCUUUGGGGGAACUAGACAUUCUUCUGCAAUGGAUGGAGGAGACAGAAUAGGAGGAAAGUGAUGCUGCUGCUAAGAAUAUUCGAGGUCAAGAGCUCCAGUCUUCAAUACCUGCAGAGGAGGCAUGACCCCAAACCACCAUCUCUUUACUGUACUAGUCUUGUGCUGGUCACAGUGUAUCUUAUUUAUGCAUUACUUGCUUCCUUGCAUGAUUGUCUUUAUGCAUCCCCAAUCUUAAUUGAGACCAUACUUGUAUAAGAUUUUUGUAAUAUCUUUCUGCUAUUGGAUAUAUUUAUUAGUUAAUAUAUUUAUUUAUUUUUUGCUAUUUAAUGUAUUUAUUUUUUUACUUGGACAUGAAACUUUAAAAAAAUUCACAGAUUAUAUUUAUAACCUGACUAGAGCAGGUGAUGUAUUUUUAUACAGUAAAAAAAAAAAACCUUGUAAAUUCUAGAAGAGUGGCUAGGGGGGUUAUUCAUUUGUAUUCAACUAAGGACAUAUUUACUCAUGCUGAUGCUCUGUGAGAUAUUUGAAAUUGAACCAAUGACUACUUAGGAUGGGUUGUGGAAUAAGUUUUGAUGUGGAAUUGCACAUCUACCUUACAAUUACUGACCAUCCCCAGUAGACUCCCCAGUCCCAUAAUUGUGUAUCUUCCAGCCAGGAAUCCUACACGGCCAGCAUGUAUUUCUACAAAUAAAGUUUUCUUUGCAUAACA